GAGGAAGAGAGGCGAGCGGAGAGUGGAGGAGGAGGCGGCGGCGGCGGGAGCGGUCCCCAGGAAUGUCGCUGCCGCCGCCACCGCCGGGGCCGCUGCCGUUGAGGAGGAGACGGAGGAGACCGACGUUGUUAGGAAGAUGAUCCCUAUGAUCUUGAAGAUGUUUCUGCACAGAAAUGAGGGAAAUACAAAGAACCAAAUACAGUUCUGAAAUUUGGGAUCUGUAUUUUGAGAUGAUUUUAUUUUCAGAAUGAGAAGCAUAUCUGGUUACCUUUAUGAAUGUAGAGACAUGAGAAGAGAGUUAUGAUGGCAAAAAACAAAGAGCCUCGUCCCCCAUCCUAUACCAUCAGUAUAGUUGGACUCUCUGGGACUGAAAAAGACAAAGGUAACUGUGGAGUUGGAAAGUCUUGUUUGUGCAAUAGAUUUGUACGCUCAAAAGCAGAUGAAUAUUAUCCAGAGCAUACUUCUGUGCUUAGCACCAUUGACUUUGGAGGACGAGUAGUAAACAAUGAUCACUUUUUGUACUGGGGUGACAUAAUACAAAAUAGUGAAGAUGGAGUAGAAUGCAAAAUUCAUGUCAUUGAACAAACAGAGUUCAUUGAUGACCAGACUUUCUUGCCUCAUCGGAGUACGAAUUUGCAACCAUAUAUAAAACGUGCAGCUGCAUCUAAAUUGCAGUCAGCAGAAAAACUAAUGUACAUUUGCACUGAUCAGCUAGGCUUAGAACAAGACUUUGAACAGAAGCAAAUGCCUGAAGGGAAGCUCAACGUAGAUGGAUUUUUAUUAUGCAUUGAUGUAAGUCAAGGAUGCAAUAGGAAGUUUGAUGAUCAACUUAAAUUUGUGAAUAACCUUUUUGUCCAGUUAUCAAAAUCAAAAAAACCUGUAAUAAUAGCAGCAACUAAAUGUGAUGAAUGCGUGGAUCAUUAUCUUAGAGAAGUUCAGGCAUUUGCUUCAAAUAAAAAGAACCUUCUUGUAGUGGAAACAUCAGCACGAUUUAAUGUCAACAUUGAAACAUGUUUUACUGCACUGGUACAAAUGUUGGAUAAAACUCGUAGCAAGCCUAAAAUUAUUCCCUAUUUGGAUGCUUAUAAAACACAGAGACAACUUGUUGUCACAGCAACAGAUAAGUUUGAAAAACUUGUGCAGACUGUGAGAGAUUAUCAUGCAACUUGGAAAACUGUUAGUAAUAAAUUAAAAAAUCAUCCUGAUUAUGAAGAAUACAUCAACUUAGAGGGAACAAGAAAGGCCAGAAAUACAUUCUCAAAACAUAUAGAACAACUUAAACAGGAACAUAUAAGAAAAAGGAGAGAAGAGUAUAUAAAUACUUUACCAAGAGCUUUUAACACUCUUUUGCCAAAUCUAGAAGAGAUUGAACAUUUGAAUUGGUCAGAAGCUUUGAAGUUAAUGGAAAAGAGAGCAGAUUUCCAGUUAUGUUUUGUGGUGCUAGAAAAAACUCCUUGGGAUGAAACUGACCAUAUAGACAAAAUUAAUGAUAGGCGGAUUCCAUUUGACCUCCUGAGCACUUUAGAAGCUGAAAAAGUCUAUCAGAACCAUGUACAGCAUCUGAUAUCCGAGAAGAGGAGGGUGGAAAUGAAGGAAAAAUUCAAAAAGACUUUGGAAAAAAUUCAAUUCAUUUCACCAGGGCAGCCAUGGGAGGAAGUUAUGUGCUUUGUUAUGGAGGAUGAAGCCUACAAAUAUAUCACUGAGGCUGAUAGCAAAGAGGUAUAUGGUAGGCAUCAGCGAGAAAUAGUUGAAAAAGCCAAAGAAGAGUUUCAAGAAAUGCUUUUUGAGCAUUCUGAACUUUUUUAUGAUUUAGAUCUUAAUGCAACACCUAGUUCAGAUAAAAUGAGUGAAAUUCAUACAGUUCUGAGUGAAGAACCUAGAUAUAAAGCUUUACAGAAACUUGCACCUGAUAGGGAAUCCCUUCUACUUAAGCAUAUAGGAUUUGUUUAUCAUCCCACUAAAGAAACAUGUCUUAGUGGCCAAAAUUGUACAGACAUUAAAGUGGAGCAGUUACUUGCUAGUAGUCUUUUACAGUUGGAUCAUGGCCGCUUAAGAUUAUAUCACGAUAGUACCAAUAUAGAUAAAGUUAACCUUUUUAUUUUAGGGAAGGAUGGCCUUGCCCAAGAACUAGCAAAUGAGAUAAGGACACAAUCCACUGAUGAUGAGUAUGCCUUAGAUGGAAAAAUUUAUGAACUUGAUCUUCGGCCGGUUGAUGCCAAAUCGCCUUACUUUUUGAGUCAGUUAUGGACUGCCGCCUUUAAACCACAUGGGUGCUUCUGUGUAUUUAAUUCCAUUGAGUCAUUGAGUUUUAUUGGGGAAUUUAUUGGGAAAAUAAGAACUGAAGCUUCUCAGAUCAGAAAAGAUAAAUACAUGGCUAAUCUUCCAUUUACAUUAAUUCUGGCUAAUCAGAGAGAUUCCAUUAGUAAGAAUCUACCAAUUCUCAGGCACCAAGGGCAGCAGUUGGCAAACAAGUUGCAAUGUCCUUUUGUAGAUGUACCUGCUGGUACAUAUCCUCGUAAAUUUAAUGAAACCCAAAUAAAGCAAGCUCUCAGAGGAGUAUUGGAAUCAGUUAAACACAAUUUGGAUGUGGUGAGCCCAAUUCCUGCCAAUAAGGACUUAUCAGAAGCUGACUUGAGAAUUGUCAUGUGCGCCAUGUGUGGAGAUCCAUUUAGUGUGGAUCUUAUUCUUUCACCCUUCCUUGAUUCUCAUUCUUGCAGUGCUGCUCAAGCUGGACAGAAUAAUUCCCUAAUGCUUGAUAAAAUCAUUGGUGAAAAAAGGAGGCGAAUACAGAUCACAAUAUUAUCAUACCACUCUUCAAUUGGAGUAAGAAAAGAUGAACUAGUUCAUGGGUAUAUAUUAGUUUACUCUGCAAAACGGAAAGCUUCGAUGGGAAUGCUUCGAGCAUUUCUAUCAGAAGUUCAAGACACCAUUCCUGUACAGCUGGUGGCAGUUACUGACAGCCAAGCAGAUUUUUUUGAAAAUGAGGCUAUCAAAGAGUUAAUGACUGAAGGAGAACACAUUGCAACUGAGAUCACUGCUAAAUUUACAGCACUGUAUUCUUUAUCUCAGUAUCAUCGGCAAACUGAGGUCUUUACUCUGUUUUUUAGUGAUGUUCUAGAGAAAAAAAAUAUGAUAGAAAAUUCUUAUUUGUCUGAUAAUACAAGGGAAUCAACCCAUCAAAGUGAAGAUGUUUUUCUACCAUCUCCCAGAGACUGUUUUCCCUAUAAUAACUACCCUGAUUCAGAUGAUGACACAGAAGCACCACCUCCUUAUAGUCCAAUUGGGGAUGAUGUACAGUUGCUUCCAACACCUAGUGACCGUUCCAGAUAUAGAUUAGAUUUGGAAGGAAAUGAGUAUCCUAUUCAUAGUACCCCAAACUGUCAUGACCAUGAACGCAACCAUAAAGUGCCUCCACCUAUUAAACCUAAACCAGUUGUACCUAAGACAAAUGUGAAAAAACUCGAUCCAAACCUUUUAAAAACAAUUGAAGCUGGUAUUGGUAAAAAUCCAAGAAAGCAGACUUCCCGGGUGCCUUUGGCACAUCCUGAAGAUAUGGAUCCUUCAGAUAACUAUGCGGAACCCAUUGAUACAAUUUUCAAACAGAAGGGCUAUUCUGAUGAGAUUUAUGUUGUCCCAGAUGAUAGUCAAAAUCGUAUUAAAAUUCGAAACUCAUUUGUAAAUAACACCCAAGGAGAUGAAGAAAAUGGGUUUUCUGAUAGAACCUCAAAAAGUCAUGGGGAACGGAGGCCUUCAAAAUACAAAUAUAAAUCUAAAACCUUGUUUAGUAAAGCCAAGUCAUACUAUAGAAGAACACAUUCAGAUGCCAGUGAUGAUGAGGCUUUCACCACUUCUAAAACAAAAAGAAAAGGAAGACAUCGUGGAAGUGAAGAAGAUCCACUUCUUUCUCCUGUUGAAACUUGGAAAGGUGGUAUUGAUAAUCCUGCAAUCACUUCUGACCAGGAGUUAGAUGAUAAGAAGAUGAAGAAGAAAACCCACAAAGUGAAAGAAGAUAAAAAGCAGAAAAAGAAAACUAAGAACUUCAAUCCACCAACACGUAGAAAUUGGGAAAGUAAUUACUUUGGGAUGCCCCUCCAGGAUCUGGUUACAGCUGAGAAGCCCAUACCACUAUUUGUUGAGAAAUGUGUGGAAUUUAUUGAAGAUACAGGGUUAUGUACCGAAGGACUCUACCGUGUCAGCGGGAAUAAAACUGACCAAGACAAUAUUCAAAAGCAGUUUGAUCAAGAUCAUAAUAUCAAUCUAGUGUCAAUGGAAGUAACAGUAAAUGCUGUAGCUGGAGCCCUUAAAGCUUUCUUUGCAGAUCUGCCAGAUCCUUUAAUUCCAUAUUCUCUUCAUCCAGAACUAUUGGAAGCAGCAAAAAUCCCGGAUAAAACAGAACGUCUUCAUGCCUUGAAAGAAAUUGUUAAGAAAUUUCAUCCUGUAAACUAUGAUGUAUUCAGAUACGUGAUAACACAUCUAAACAGGGUUAGUCAGCAACAUAAAAUCAACCUAAUGACAGCAGACAACUUAUCCAUCUGUUUUUGGCCAACCUUGAUGAGACCUGAUUUUGAAAAUCGAGAGUUUCUGUCUACUACUAAGAUUCAUCAAUCUGUUGUUGAAACAUUCAUUCAGCAGUGUCAGUUUUUCUUUUACAAUGGAGAAAUUGUAGAAACGACAAACAUUGUGGCUCCUCCACCACCUUCAAACCCAGGACAGUUGGUGGAACCAAUGGUGCCACUUCAGUUGCCGCCACCAUUGCAACCUCAGCUGAUACAACCACAAUUACAAACGGAUCCUCUUGGUAUUAUAUGAGUAGGAAGUGAUUGCAAACAGGCUGGAUUUGGACAAAAAGCAAAUCUAGACAUGCAUGUUUCAGGGUUCAGUAGUAUACUUCAUGUUUCAUACAGAUAAUUCACAUUCAAAAUUACAUUUUCUCUUUGAACUAGAUGGUAUUCCUUAUUCACUUACAUUACAAAUCUAAGACCAUGUGAUAAGCAUGACUGGAGAGGUUUAAUUUUUAUAAACAAAAAUAGCUAUAAAGUACAAAGCUGCUGCUGCAUGCAACCUUAUUGCAAUCAGUAUAUCAUUCCUGUGGCAAUUUCUGUCACCUUAUAUUGUGAAUAAAAUUUUUCUAUAGAAAUUAAAUGAUUUAAAAACUCACCUAUAUGAAACAUUUAAUGCUUUUCAGCCUGCUUUCUGGCUGAUUUUGUUAUUUGAUGUGCUAAUUUGGGCAACUUAAUUUACAUUCUGGCAGUCGGUGUAGAUAACUAAAAGCCCAGUUAAGUAUUUUAUAAUUUCAGGCUACUGAGGCCAUGCUUGGGAUGUUGUUUGAAAGAAAGAAAAAAUACACUUGACAUAUUUCACAUUUCUGUACCUUCAUCUUUACUUCCAAGUAAACCCGUGGAUGAUUUGAUGAGGGAUAAAUGAACCUAUUUCUUUUACACACAUACCAAGGACAUGCUUGUGGCUAAAGUGAGUUGAUAAUGUUGUGCAAAGGAUAGUUGUCACCAACUCAUUUCUUUAUGGUCCAUAAUGAAAUAAAAAUUUUGUAUACUGUUAAUUCUGUAAACAGAUGCAUGUUCAAAAGAUCUAUGAUGGUCUUGUAAUCUUAAUCUAAUAUAUUUUAGAUAUUUUAAUUUUUUCCCUCUUGGGGAACACAUUUAGUAUAGUGUAGAAAAUACUUCCAUGACAUUUUCAUAUAAGGUUAUAUAACUUUUCAUACAUAAACAUGAAAUUUGUUGUAGAAAAUUCUUUAAACCAAACAUUUAAAUCUAGGACUUCAAUUUAAUUUGUUCCUUGAAUCUAUUUUUAUGUGGCCCUUAAAAAAUAUCCAAAAAACCCAUUGCUAAUAUAGCAAUAAAAAUACUUUGGGUACUGACAGACUCUUUGGAGUGUUUAUAUUACAAAUUUGUAUUCAUAUUCUUUUCUGUGAUGUGUUGUACUAAAAUCCAAAAUGGCUUUUGCACCAUUUUUAAGCCAAUUUUUUCCUUUGAUGUUGGUACCAGAAUUACUAUAAGUGACUGCUGCUUUUGGGGGUAAACAUUUUGUUAGUGAAGAUAAAACCAGAACACUAAAUUAUGGAUAAAAUUUUCAGAAUAGGUGGCACAGGUAAAUUUCACUAGGUUAUAUUUUGUGUAGUAAAGAAAAAAAUUAUUUGGUCAAUGUUAUCUUAAUUCAUACUACAAUUUAAGAUUAUCUUAUGUGUAUUAUAGUAAAUAGAUGAUUUUCAGAUUCAAGGCUCCUAAGAGUUUGAUUUGCUCUGUUUUUUCCUAAAAUAAAUAUUGUCUCUCCCAACUGUUAAGUUCUAGGUAUUGUACUUCCAAUUUUAACUUCAGAACCAAGAUGUUGGCAUGAACCAGGCUGCUGUUGAAGUACAUGUAUAUUAUAAAUUAUCUUAUUUGUGUUAUACUCUUACAUGUUAUCUUUUCUAAGAAAACAAAGUCCCUAUUAUUCCUAUUGCAAAGCACACAGGAAUUAAGAAAGUACAGUAAUUUUUAAAAAAAAAUCCGGUAAAUGUAGUAUUCUUAACCUGUUCUAUAUUACUUAUACCUAUUGUCUAUAUAGCUUUAAUUUAUAGUUGUCAGUUUAACUAUUGGCAUGUCUGGCAAAGAAAAUUAAACUUUAAGAGUUUUAUAAACUGUUUCUAGGUUGCUAAAGAAUUUAUUUUUCUACUAUAUAUGGUAUAGACAAAGCAUCAAACUAUGUACAGGAAAAAAGCCUGACUAUUUCUAUUUGGAAGUAGGCUGAAAAGAGAAUUUUCAAAACUGUUCGUGUCUUCAGUUCAUUCUGUCAUAACUUUGCUAUUGUAAUAUGUGAAUACCAGUUUAUUUAAGCUGUUCUCUUUUAUACUGUAUUAAUUUAAUGUUCAUCUGCGUUUAGUACCAUUUUUGUUAUUAAAACUGGCAUUUACCGUUUUUCACAUUAACCCACCUUGCACCUUCCCCCAAACUUAUCUCCACUUUUCUAUGCAUUCUAUCAUUGAUUUGACACACUUCAUAGUGAGUCAUUUAAAUACUCUACGUUUGGUUCAAUUAACCAGUAGGUUACAGUUAUUGAAAAUUAAAGUACAGUUUAAAGCUCAGUCUGUUACACUGAAUUGAUUGUGUUUGUUUUUGCCAAGGGUUUAGAUAUGCUUUUAAAUAUUAGAAACAUCUAAGAACAGAAUAACAUAAUUAAACUUUUUUCUGGUAAGUUACUGGAAGGUUUCACUGUUUAGGGACCUAUCAUAUGAGACUUCUUAAAGGAUUAAAAGAAUAGGAUAGUCUCAUAAUUGUGAGUAAACAUCAAGGCAUUAUAUUUUACAAUACUGAAUAAAAUUUCAUCUACACACAUGUUGCCAUUGUUUCAUUUAAGGUUCAGUGCUUAUAGUUAACUACAAUAUUGGACCUAACAGGAUCUAGAUUAGCAAUAUAAAGAAGCAUAGUGGUACUCUGUUUCACACUUUCAGUAGAUUUAUUAGAAGUCAAAUUCUAUUCAACAGACACUUAUUAGGAUAUACAACUAAUUUAAGAAUAAAAUUCCAGGCACAAUAUAUUUUUUUUAAAUGGUAUUUGUUAGUAGUGCUUCUUCCCCUUAACAUUUACAGUGUAAAUACUGCAGGUAACCGCAAUCUAAGUUAGCCAAAAAGCAGCUUUUUUUCCCAUACUGUAUGUAAAUAAUGUAGACCUGGGUUUUUUUGUUUAUUUGGGUUUGUUUUUUUUUUUGAGGUACUGGAAUCUAAUUAAUAUCUCUUAGGUAUCAACAAAAGGGAACAAUUGGAAUGAGAAUUUAGGCCUUAGCUUCCAUGGUGAUUUUUAGUUUUUUAUACAGUAAUAAUUGUGAUGCUAUUUGUCAACUGGAUAUAAAUACACAUAUAAUUUUAAAAAGUCAAAAGUGCUUUUGUUUCUUUGUUUAAUGUAAUUUUUGUGCUUCACCUACAGGAUGCUGCAGUAAAUUAAAUAUCAGUGAAGCUUCUGAUGUAUAAAGAAUGCUAUGAAUAAAACAUUAAGAAGCUGUGUAAUUUUAAGUUAUAGUUGCCUCUAUUUUUACCAUUUCAUUGGUAAAAAUUAGCUAAUUUUUUUCAAGUGAAAUGAAAAAUAAAAAUAUAAAUUUAUCAAUAUGAUGGAAAUCUUAUUAAGGAGAUGUAUUAUUGAAUUUUCACUGUACCUGAAAAGGAGAUUCAAAAUUUUUUCUGGGGAUGUAUAUAGGUGAAAAUUUGAUUUUUUAAAUUAUCAGGAAAACAAGAUAAUGCACAGAUUUCUAAGACUAAGAUCUUACCUGGAUGUGAUUUUUGAGCUGUGGCUAGACAUUCUUUAGAGCCACUGGAAAUAUUUUGAAAACUAUUCUAGUUAUAGCAGAGCUGCUAAUAUUAACGAAUAUAUUUGUGUCUUCAUGGUUUGUGACUAUUAGGCCAAAUUUUGUGGUAUAUGUUGUCAGUCUGGAUCUGGUGAGGUCUGUUCAACAUGAAUCUUUGUGUUAUCUUGAAUUUAGUAGUUUCAAGGUACUUAAAUUCUUAACAGUUUCUAAUUUGUUUCAAUACAUAUGGGACAUGGUUGAUUUUUUUACUGUAUUAGAACUCUUGGAAGUUCUUAGCCUUUUCAGGUUAUGAAAUACCUGAAAGUAAAAUUUUCUAAGAUUUAAUAAGGGAAGAUACUAUUCAAAUCAUUUUCUUAGGAUAGCAUCUUUACAUACAAUGAGAGGAUUGUACAAGCAUUAAUCUCAUAUUCCAACAUCCAGUUACUUGAUGUGAUCCAAGUACCCUGGUCUUUUUGAAGCAGUUAAAAUCUAAUUAAUUAACUUUGGGAGUCUUCACUAUUCAAUUGAUCCUCAUCAUUGUCCUAUUUGCAUGACUCCAUUUUUUCCUCCACUAUAUGAGUUUUCUUUGUCAGGGGGAGAGGAGUGGGAAGAGUCACAGAAUCUCAUAUUCACAUCUUAAUUAAAUUGUGUGAAAUUAGUCUUUUGUGGAAAUUCUGUAGGCAGUAUGAUUUUGAAAAGCUAACCAAUGAUAAUUAGCAUUUUAGUUAAUACUAAAUGCAUAAAAUUAUAACCCUUGAAAUUAAUUUGGUGCUGGCAGUUCUGGUUUAGUCAUUUUUACCAGUAGUUAGUAGUAUUAAGACCUGCAGUAUAUGCACUUUUUGAGUAGCUGUCAAAUAAUUGUAGUUGAGAAACAACUUGUUUAUUCUCACAAUUCAGAUUUUCUAUUCAGUUUUGUCUCAAAUAGUAAGUUAUUGUGAACAAUUUAAUAACGGCCCUCCUGUUCUAGUUUGCCUAAUAUUUUAGUUAAGAUUUAGUGUUUUAACCUAUUUUUUUAAGUUUAUUUUUUGUAUUAGAUUUUAUUUGAAUAAGUUAUGUGGGUUUAGUAAUUGACCUAUUUAUUCAUUGCUUCACUAAUUCAUCCAGAUUAGUUUUAAGUGUGUAUAUGUAUUUGCUCACCAGAUCAUUUUCUUGGGACCUUGAACUGUGAAUGUUUUGUCCUAACCAUUUAAUAUUUUCUAGGUACUUGCUGCAAGUUCUUGAACUAUUUUACCAGCUUUAACUUUGGGGCUCUUAGUUUCUUUUCUCCAGAUUCUUGUUAUUUUAUUUUAUCCAAAUAAAUAUUUAGGUGUUCUAAGAA